AGAACCAGGAAGGCGCUGAGCUUAAACUGAAGCAAGUUCGGUGGACGCCGGCGGCGCCCUGAUCUAAAGAAACGACUCAGGGACUGCGGCGCUUGCACGUCAACGGGAGGUGUGAGCCCAAAGGUCUGGACCCAGAAAUGGGACGUCGGUCAUCAGAUACUGAAGAAGAAAGCAGAAGCAAGAGAAAAAAGAAACACCGUAGACGGUCCUCCUCGAGCAGUUCUUCAGAUAGUAGAACAUACAGCCGAAAGAAAGGAGGAAGGAAAUCAAGAUCAAAGUCAAGAUCUUGGUCCAGAGAUCUUCAGCCUCGUUCACAUUCUUAUGAUAGAAGACGCAGGCAUCGAUCAAGCAGUAGCUCUUCUUAUGGCUCCAGAAGGAAACGAAGUCGAAGUCGUUCAAGGGGUCGAGGGAAAUCCUAUAGAGUUCAGAGGUCUAGGUCAAAAAGCAGAACAAGAAGGUCCAGGUCAAGACCUCGUCUCCGUUCUCAUAGUCGUAGCAGUGAAAGGUCCAGUCACAGAAGAACGCGUAGUCGGUCUCGGGAUAGAGAACGACGUAAGGGCAGAGAUAAAGAGAAAAGAGAAAAGGAGAAGGAUAAAGGGAAGGACAAGGAAUUACAUAACAUCAAACGUGGGGAAUCUGGAAACAUCAAAGCUGGAUUAGAACAUCUGCCACCAGCUGAACAGGCCAAAGCCAGACUACAGCUGGUUCUUGAAGCUGCUGCAAAAGCUGAUGAAGCAUUGAAAGCCAAAGAAAGAAAUGAGGAAGAAGCAAAGAGAAGAAAGGAGGAAGGUAAAGGCAUGUGUUCAUUUUUCUCUGAGAAAUCACUAUUUGGCUGUAUUUCCUGAAUAGACCGUAGAAUAUAAUCUAAUGCCUUAAGGGUUACUUCAUGCUGUUUCAUGAACCAAAACUAUGACACAAUAGCACACUAUAUUCAUUGUCUUGGACACUAAUGUUUGCUCUCAUAAGAUUAGUUUAUAAGCAUGCUAUUAUAUAUUCUGGGAAAUUGGGAGGAGAUAAGAUUAUAUAGUAGUGCUGAUGUUGGUUUGUUCCUUCUGACUUUUAUAGUUAAAAAAUUAUCAAAAUCAGUCACAGAAAUAGAUUGAACCUUAUCCAUAGAUUUUGAAAUAUUUCAGUAGUGAUGAAGAAAAGUCCUCUUGCCAAUAAAACUUUUUUAAAGUUGAGAGAACAUUGAAAUUCAAAAUGUCAUAAAUAGUCAUAUGAAAUCCAUGUCUUCAUUUUUAAAGAUAUUCUUUUUAAAAAACAACAUUUAGGCCAUUCCCCCAAAAUAUUAUCUAAACAAAUCUAACACAUUUUUAUCUCCUCUAACAAAUUUUUAUUUUCCCCUUAAUUUGCUAUCUGUGAUUUAUGUGAGUGAAAAUUUUGCCUUUUUUUCUUCACGGGGGAUUAUAUACAUAUACUGUUCUAAAUUACAGUGCUUAAAGCAAGAUUCAGGCAAAUCUUUCUCAGUGAGUUAAGUUGAUGAUCUGCUUAGAAUGGCAAUCAUGUCACUUUAUUGGCUAAUUUCACAGGGUAGCUAUUUCCUCUUGUGAGCUUUUGAGAAGUUGAAGUCUGAUAAUAUGUGCCAGAAUUUGGACUUUUGAGUGCUGUAGUCAAAAUCUGAAAGUUGAAAUUUUUGCCUUAGUAGGUACCUGUGUUUUAUUGUAACAACCAGAAGAUAAUCUGAACUUCCCAGCAACUACAUGGAAGCUGAGAUUCAGUAAAACCCAAAGUAUAAUGGUUUAGAAUGCUUAAAACCCAUCAGAGCCAUCCUCAAAACCAAGCGAAAAAAAAAAAAAAAACUGUAGAUUUAAGUGGCAGAUCCCUACAAAUAAGUAGAUUCAAACUAAAUGUGGAUGAAUUUGUACACAUAUAGUAUAGUGUUCUUACCUUACUUGACCCCCAAAUAUCCUGGCUUUAUGCUCUUUUCCGGGAUCAACUAAUUUUAUGGUAUACUGAGAAAAAAAUGAAUUUCAGUAGCAAGAUUCCUCAGUAGAAUUACCUUCUUUUGGAUCUCUUGGCAUUGUUAAUGAAAGCAAGCUAUCUGAUUUCAGUUAUCCUUAUAAUGUGCCCAUAGUACAAACAGACAUAAGACUAAAUGCAAAUGUGUCUAAGCAAAUUAUAAUUUUUAAGUACUGCUAUGUUGUGUGGCAUUCUGAUCAAUGUAACUAAUUAAUAACAUAAUGGCCCUUAUAAAACUCUGUGGUACCGUAAAUCACGUGUAUAGUACUUAUGACCAAGCAAUACAGUGAAAAUAUGUUGUAGUGGUUAUUAGCCUAAUCCUAUUAAUUCAGAUCUUAAUUGGAAUCUUAAUCAGUUGAAAAUGAAUGGCAGUGAGAGUAAUCACAGAUAUUGAAAUUUCAAGGUGAUUUGUUUUUAUGAAAAAAAUAAUAUGAAUGCUUAUCUUAGCAAAAGAAACUUUUUUAAUACUUCAGAACUCCUCAUUUACAUGUUGACAGUUGAUAUUUCUACAGCUCUCUUGUUUUCAUUAAAUUAGCUCUAAGCAUCUUUUAAGACAUUUGCUUAAGAAUUUCUUAAGUAACUAUAGAUACUUGAACAUUAUAAUUCUUUGUAAUUUUUAAUUUAGACUUUUCACUAAAUCACACUGACCUUAUACGUAGUCUGCAAUAUACAGUACCUUUUUUCUUUCAGUUCCUGAGAAUUGUUGAAAAAGCAUAUUCCUCCAAUCAUAGCUGUUUUAAUUAGCAUCUUUAAAAAUCUAGCAUUCUAACUAGAGUAUAAACUACAGGAUUACAGAGGACUUAAUAUCCACAAUGCCUAACACAUAGUAGAAACUCAGUUUCUUGAAUUGUUGCAUGAUGAAUGAAUAAAUCAAUGACCAAUUUCCCUUUAUUCUUUUAAAUUCAUGCUAAGUAGCUUAUUUUGAGCUUGCAACGGGAUUCCAAAUAAUCUCAUUGAAAGUAUAACCCAACUUUGUUAAGGGCUUUUCUAAGACAGGCCGUAACUAUUAAGCUAUUGCUGUAAUAAUUUAGAGCAUGCAAAAUUAAACCAAAGAAUGUCAAAAUACUGUCAAAAUUUGCUAAACUAUUUGCUAGAUUCUUUGUUGUUGUUUGCUUCCAAAUUUUUUUUCUCUUGAGUUGUCUAGAUACUUGAAUGCUAUCAAAUUAACAGUUCCCUGAGAGUGAUUAAUGUAUAAGCUACAUUUAUUUUAUUUCAUAUAAUUAGUCUAACUGCAAAUUGAAACCUUAGAUCAGUAUGCAUGUGUGUAUAUAGUUCUGUAUCUGAAAGAAUAAAAAUCCUUUAUUUUCAGUCUGUAAGCCACUAGUAAUUCACUCUGUCACAUCAUUUAUACAAUUCAUCUCUUAAUUUCUCAUCAUGCUGAUGUGCAAUACAGAGUUGAAAGCAUUGCGAAAAUGUAGAUAAAUGUUGUCUACCCAGCUCCCUUUAUCCACUCUCUGUUAUCUCAGAAAAGCUAUUGUAUUAGCAUAGCAAGAUCUGUGCCAUGCAAAUUCAUUCUAUUAUGCAGUCUUCCUUUGAGUGUUCUUAAAUCAAUAACAUAAUUAUGUUUGCAAGUAUUGCAUCCAAAAUAAAAGUCAGGCUGCACACCAAAA